AGUGGUAGUGCUCCAGGCUCGACGGCACCCUCACAGCGCCCGCCCGGCCCUGCCGCUCAUGGCCGCCCCGCCGCGCCCCGCGCCAUCGCCCCCCGCCCCGCGGCGCCUCGACACGAGCGACGUCCUGCAGCAGAUCAUGGCCAUCACCGACCAGAGCCUGGACGAGGCACAGGCCAGAAAGCAUGCUCUGAAUUGCCAUCGGAUGAAGCCUGCUCUGUUCAGCGUGCUCUGUGAGAUCAAGGAAAAGACAGCAUCUUCAUUUCUCACGCGUCCGUGUGAAGAGACCACCAAACAGGCUUUCUUGGUAAGCAUCCGUGGCAUUCAAGACGAAGAUCCCCCUGACGCCCAGCUCCUGAGGCUGGAUAACAUGCUGCUGGCUGAGGGCGUGUGCAGGCCCGAGAAGAGAGGAAGAGGAGGAGCGGUGGCCAGGGCCGGCACAGCAACACCAGGUGGCUGUCCAAAUGACAAUAGCAUUGAGCACUCUGACUACAGGGCCAAGCUGUCCCAGAUCCGACAGAUUUACCACUCUGAGCUAGAGAAAUAUGAACAGGCCUGUCGUGAGUUCACCACGCACGUCACCAACCUCCUCCAGGAGCAGAGCAGGAUGAGGCCUGUCUCCCCUAAGGAGAUUGAGCGCAUGGUCGGCGCCAUUCACGGCAAGUUCAGCGCCAUCCAGAUGCAGUUGAAGCAGAGCACCUGUGAGGCAGUGAUGACCCUGCGUUCGCGGCUGCUCGAUGCCAGGCGCAAGCGGCGGAAUUUCAGCAAGCAGGCGACGGAAGUGCUGAAUGAGUAUUUUUACUCCCAUCUGAACAACCCUUACCCCAGCGAAGAAGCCAAAGAAGAGCUGGCCAGGAAGGGCGGCCUCACCAUCUCCCAGGUCUCUAACUGGUUUGGCAACAAAAGAAUCCGGUAUAAAAAGAACAUGGGGAAGUUUCAAGAAGAGGCUACCAUUUACACGGGUAAAACGGCUGUGGAUACCACGGAAGUUGGGGUCCCAGGGAACCACGCCAGCUGCCUGUCAACACCUAGCUCCGGCUCCUCUGGACCCUUCCCGCUGCCCAGCGCUGGGGACGCCUUCCUCACCCUGCGGACUCUGGCCUCUCUCCAGCCUCCUCCUGGGGGAGGCUGCCUGCAGUCCCAGGCCCAGGGUAGCUGGCAGGGGGCCACCCCCCAACCUGCAACUGCCUCACCUGCUGGAGACCCUGGCAGCAUCAACUCCAGUACAUCUAAUUAAGUUUGGGGGAUAAGCAGGAAAGAGCGCUGCGUGAGCUGCCAUGUAUCGCCAGCCGUUGCUUUGUUACUGAACGUGCCGCCGACGACCUCAGAAAACCCAGAUGGGUGGUGGUGCCCAUGAGCCCCUGCUCCUCAGCCAGGCCCGUGGCGCCGGCUCAUGUGUCUGCUGCGACUCGAGAUGGCCUGAAACGCCACUCAUUCUCCCACUUCAGUUCGUUUUUUUGACAGUAAUUUUAUGGUAACGCUAUGAAUUGAAUUGUCUGUUCUAGGACUGGGCACAGAUUUUCCCAUUAAAAUUUUUGACUUAUUUUAA